CUGGCCGGCCGUCGCGGACUCGGGAGAUGGAGGAAAAGGAGAUAUUACGGCGGCAGAUCCGCCUACUGCAGGGUCUGAUUGAUGACUACAAAACCCUCCACGGCAAUGCCCCGGCCCCUGGUACCCCAGCAGCUUCUGGGUGGCAGCCACCCACUUACCACAGUGGCAGAGCCUUUAGUGCCCGCUACCCUCGUCCAAGCCGGAGGGGCUACUCUUCCCACCAUGGGCCUUCGUGGCGCAAGAAAUACUCCCUCGUGAAUCGGCCCCCGGGACCCUCAGACCCUCCUGCCGACCAUGCUGUGCGGCCGUUGCACGGGGCCCGGGGGGGCCAGCCUCCUGUCCCGCAGCAGCAUGUCCUUGAGAGACAGGUCCAGCUCAGUCAGGGUCAGAACGUGGUCAUCAAAGUUAAACCGCCAUCAAAGUCUGGCUCUGCCAGUGCCUCAGGGGCCCAGCGGGGCUCUUUGGAAGAAUUUGAGGAAACCCCCUGGAGUGACCAAAGGCCCCGGGAAGGUGAAGGUGAGCCCCCUCGGGGACAGCUGCAGCCCUCGAGGCCAACAAGAGCCAGGGGGACCUGCAGUGUGGAAGAUCCUCUUCUGGUCUGCCAGAAGGAGCCUGGUAAGCCCAGGAUGGUGAAGUCAGUGGGCAGUGUGGGCGACAGCCCCCGGGAGCCCCGCCGGACAGUCAGUGAGAGUGUGAUUGCCGUCAAGGCGAGCUUCCCAUCCUCCGCUCUGCCCCCACGCACUGGCGUGGCCCUGGGCCGGAAGCUGGGUUCUCAUUCCGUGGCCAGCUGUGCUCCACAGCUCCUUGGGGACAGGAGAGUAGAUGCUGGCCACACAGAUCAGCCAGUUCCGUCUGGCUCAGUGGGGGGCCCCGCCAGACCGGCCUCAGGACCCAGGCAGGCCCGGGAGGCCUCGCUGGUUGUGACCUGUCGAACUAACAAGUUCCGGAAAAACAACUACAAAUGGGUGGCUGCCUCCUCGAAGAGUCCCCGGGUUGCUCGGAGGGCCCUCAGUCCCAGAGUGGCUGCAGAGAAUGUGUGCAAGGCCUCUGCUGGCAUGGCAAACAAGGUGGAGAAGCCGCAGCUCAUAGCUGACCCAGAGCCCAAGCCCAGGAAGCCAGCCACGUCCUCCAAGCCAGGGUCUGCCCCCAGCAAGUACAAGUGGAAGGCCUCCAGCCCCUCUGCCUCCUCCUCUUCCUCCUUCCGUUGGCAGUCGGAGGCCAGCAGCAAGGACCAUGCCUCCCAGCUCUCCCCAGUCCUGUCUAGGUCCCCGUCGGGGGACAGACCAGCAGUAGGACACAGUGGCUUGAAGCCCCUCUCUGGGGAGACCCCGCUCUCGGCUUACAAAGUGAAGAGCCGCACCAAGAUCAUCCGGAGACGCAGCAGCACAAGCCUUCCUGGAGACAAGAAAAGCGGCACCUCACCUGCCGCCACCGCCAAGAGCCACCUCAGCCUCCGGCGGAGACAGGCCCUCAGGGGGAAGAGCAGCCCUGUCCUGAAGAAGACCCCCAACAAGGGCCUGGUACAGGUCACCACGCACCGACUAUGUCGCCUGCCACCGAGCCGGGCCCACCUCCCCACCAAGGAAGAGUUCAAGACCAGCAAGGAGACGUGGCCGGCCAGGUCCCUGGGCCUCCUGUGUAGGGAGAAGUCACUGCAGCCCUCGCUGCGCCCAGGGGCCCUGCC